GCACAAUGGGCCAUGGAGUUCCCGUUCGAUGUGGACGCGCUGUUCCCGGAGCGGAUCACGGUGCUGGACCAGCACCUGAGGCCCCCAGCCCGCCGACCCGGAACCACAACGCCGGCCCGGUGACAGCUCAAACCCACCCUCUGGCCCUUUUCUCCCGGUUCCUCUCCAAACCUGGUCCAGGCACCACGCCCCCUUCUCACUGACUAGUGAUCGCCCCUUUUGAUGUCCAGGCCUGCCUUUUUGGUGACCUCUGACCCUGGGCCUAGUGGGAUUGAUCAGCGCUUGGAUCUGUGACCUUUCACCCCGGGCCCAAAAUGUCCCAAUCAAAGGAUGUGGUUGACCUGGCCUUUCUGCUUCCUCACAAUAACCUUAAGGGAGGAGGGAGUGUGCCACCUUGAAAGUGUUGAUCUACAGCAGCAAAUUAUGACCAUUAUAGAUGAACUGGGCAAGGCUUCUGCCAAGGCCCAGAAUCUUUCCGCUCCUAUCACUAGUGCAUCAAGGAUGCAGAGUAACCGCCAUGUUGUUUAUAUUCUCAAAGACAGUUCAGCCCGACCGGCUGGAAAAGGAGCCAUUAUUGGUUUCAUCAAAGUUGGAUACAAGAAGCUCUUUGUACUGGAUGAUCGUGAGGCUCAUAAUGAGGUAGAACCACUUUGCAUCCUGGACUUUUACAUCCAUGAGUCUGUGCAACGCCAUGGCCAUGGGCGAGAACUCUUCCAGUAUAUGUUGCAGAAGGAGCGAGUGGAACCGCACCAACUGGCAAUUGACCGACCCUCACAGAAGCUGCUGAAAUUCCUGAAUAAGCACUACAAUCUGGAGACCACAGUCCCACAGGUGAACAACUUUGUGAUCUUUGAAGGCUUCUUUGCCCAUCAACAUCCUCCAGCAAGGAAGCUGCCACCCAAGAGAGCAGAGGGAGACAUCAAGCCAUACUCCUCUAGUGACCGAGAAUUUCUGAAGGUAGCUGUGGAGCCUCCUUGGCCCCUAAACAGGGCCCCUCGCCGCGCCACACCUCCAGCCCACCCACCCCCCCGCUCCAGCAGCCUGGGAAACUCACCAGAACGAGGUCCCCUCCGCCCCUUUGUGCCAGAGCAGGAGCUGCUGCGUUCCUUGCGCCUCUGCCCCCCACACCCUACCGCCCGCCUUCUGUUGGCUGCUGACCCUGGGGGCAGCCCAGCUCAACGUCGUCGCACCAGGUAAUAGGAGUUGAAGGGCUAAGGAGCCUCACAGCUAUAAAAGAGGAUGUUAGAAAUGGCAAAGGGCAAUUUGAAUCCAUCAGAGAGAUGGAUCAAUAAGAUGGGUGGCUUGGGGGGGGUCCUGAAACCUUUCAAGAAAAAUAUUUGUGCAAGUGAUCUGGGAAAAAAAUGCAGUGAAGGAGCAGAAUAGGACCUUAUAUGGAGCCUAGGGACCCUGGCUUUAAUGUGAGAGUUAUGUGGAAUGGUAGGAAGAACACCGAGAUCCAUCGAGUUGGGGGAACAGAGCCUUCUAAGAUUGGGAAAAUCUUCGCUUAAUACUUGCUGGGGAAGGGGCAGUGUCUGACAGAGAGUGGGAAGCCACUGGCUUGUGUGCCAAGAGUCCAUCGCAGCAGGCAGGGAGUGGGCAUUUCCUUUAUUUCUCUCCCUUUCUCUUCACCUCUGACUUCUCUGUUUUUCUCUCCCCCGCCCCCCGCCAUUUCCCAUCUCCCUUCCUCCCAUCCAUAACAUCCUUCCACAGCUCCCUUCCCCGCUCUGAGGAGAGUCGAUACUAACAGCUACCCUCUCCCUGCCCUGGGAGACCUGGGGUGGGCAGGGAACCCCUCCCUGAGAACCUCAGACCCACUCUUCCAUUGCAUCCUGUAGGACCCAGUGGAACCUGACAGAGCCCAUAGGAUUCCCUCUUCUACUUUCUUAGACAGCAGGGAUGUCAGGGUCUCAAACUGCCUAACACUUUGUAGCUUUUCUUAACACAAAAGCACCCCUUCUCUCCUAACUUGGGCUCUGAAUACUUUCCCAACAGGAAGUCUGAUCUGUUGCCAGACUUCUUGGUUAGAUGGCUCAUACAUUUAUCUAGAGAAGCACACUCUUGCUUGCUGUCAAACUUUAGACCACCAUGGAAGGUCUAAGGGCAUCCUGUGCCAGGGAAACUUUUUAAGGAAUUUUAUCUAUGGGAUAAACCCCAUAUUCCCUCUAGUGUCUACUGGUGGCUCUAAUACUGCUUUGUGCUGCCUGCCACACUUGCCCUUUGAGCCUGCGAAUGGCCGCUAGUGAGCAAGCUCUGCUUCAGAGCAGUCUAGUUAGGUAGAACAGGGACUUACCAGCUUCCCAAAGGGAUCUACUCACCAUUGCCAAACUCUUCAUUUCCACAUUUUGUGUAGGUGUCAGGGAACCCCAAACUGGUGUUGCUUUGGGGUCUCUAAAGGAGAUUGGCUGACACCACCAUUUCCCCCAGAUCCAGAUUCUCUGAGGGAGGUUGUUUCUUGAGAGUAGAUCCAGAGUGUCAAGGAUCUGUUAGAUCCUGGAAUCCCUUCUUGCAUCCAUCCCUCCCUGGUAGCUAGGUCCCGAUAUACUCCUGUCUUGUGAGAUUGUCGAGAUGAGAUGGGGGACCACUCUUCCUCUGUCCUUCCUCUCUCCUUUCCUCCAUAGCAAGGACGACCUUCCCUGCUCCAUGCCCAGAGUAUAGCUAGAUCCCUUCCCCUCCCUACCCUCUGAAUGUGUGCUAGAUCAGGUGCCCCACUGUGUUUCCUGAAAUCCUUGGGAGCCGGAUCUCCCCAUCUCCCCUACUCACUCUUCCCUUUUCUUCUCUCAGUGUUGUCUGAAUAAAGUGUGAAAUCUUUUGUGUUUUCUAAA